AUUCCUGAGGAGGACUGCCGGUCGUUCGGACGUCUUGCCUGUCGCUGGAGGAGAGGUCCGGGCUCUCCAGGAAGGUGGCUGCGGCGACAAAAUGAAGAUAUUCGUGGGCAACGUCGACGGGGCGGAUACGACUCCGGAGGAGCUGGCAGCCCUCUUUGCGCCCUACGGCACGGUCAUGAGCUGCGCCGUCAUGAAACAGUUCGCCUUCGUGCACAUGCGCGAGAACGCGGGCGCGCUGCGCGCCAUCGAAGCCCUGCACGGCCACGAGCUGCGGCCGGGGCGCGCGCUCGUGGUGGAGAUGUCGCGCCCAAGGCCUCUUAAUACUUGGAAGAUUUUCGUGGGCAAUGUGUCGGCUGCAUGCACGAGCCAGGAACUGCGCAGCCUCUUCGAGCGCCGCGGACGCGUCAUCGAGUGUGACGUGGUGAAAGGCAAACGAAUGCACGUGCAGUUGUCCACCAGCCGGCUUAGGACUGCGCCCGGGAUGGGAGACCAGAGCGGCUGCUAUCGGUGCGGGAAAGAGGGGCACUGGUCCAAAGAGUGUCCGAUAGAUCGUUCAGGCCGCGUGGCAGACUUGACCGAGCAAUAUAAUGAGCAAUACGGAGCAGUGCGUACGCCUUACACCAUGAGCUAUGGGGAUUCAUUGUAUUACAACAACGCGUACGGAGCGCUCGAUGCCUACUACAAGCGCUGCCGUGCUGCCCGGUCCUAUGAGGCAGUGGCAGCUGCAGCUGCCUCCGUGUAUAAUUACGCAGAGCAGACCCUGUCCCAGCUGCCACAAGUCCAGAAUACAGCCAUGGCCAGUCACCUCACCUCCACCUCUCUCGAUCCCUACGAUAGACACCUGUUGCCGACCUCAGGAGCUGCUGCCACAGCUGCUGCUGCAGCAGCAGCCGCUGCUGCUGUUACUGCAGCUUCCACUUCAUAUUACGGGCGGGAUCGGAGCCCCCUGCGUCGCGCUACAGCCCCAGUCCCCACUGUUGGAGAGGGCUACGGUUACGGGCAUGAGAGUGAGUUGUCCCAAGCUUCAGCAGCCGCGCGGAAUUCUCUGUACGACAUGGCCCGGUAUGAGCGGGAGCAGUAUGCCGAUCGGGCGCGGUACUCAGCCUUUUAAAGCUUGAGGUGGGAUGUGUGUGGGCUGAAAUUCCGAGCUGCGGUUGUGCAUGAGAAUACACCCUUCGUGGUACCCCAUCUCCGGGACGUUCUCGGCUCUGUGCGUUCAGUCCCUCAGGAACCGUGGACCUUAAUUUACCUUGCUAAGUUCAGACCUUCUCUUCCUUUCCUUUCCUUUCCUCUCCUGCCCAUUUUCCUGUUCUUCUGUCCUUCAAUACUUCUGUAGCUUCCCAUUCAUGUUCUCUUCUCCCAGCAGGCCUCAUUGUGUGCAGAAACUGUGGUGGGGGCUGUGCUGUCUCCUCCCUGCCUCCUGCCUCCUGCGGCUGUUGGAUUUGGGAAUGACCUUGGUGAGAGUCUCACUGCUCCAGGGUCUCUUUUUGGUCCAAAGGCUAGACCUAUAGAGUUGGAUCACUUUUUUUCUUUCCGGUGAAAUAAAUGGUUUUUCAACUUA